GAAACAGUGUGGGGCCUAGAGCGCUGGGUGGGCGCGUUCUGCGGCCUGAGCAGGGACGGGUAGUGAAGCGGUUACGCCCCUUCUUCGCGUCUUGGCGGGAGCCUGACGCCCCGCUUCUCCCCUAACGAGGUGUCCCACCGGCGCCCGCCGAGGCCUAGGCCUCCGCAGCCGCCCUCCGUCUCCUCAGCCCCGACGCUGCGCCUUGGGCCUUGUGCGCAUUUUUUUCGGGGGAAAACUGAGGCUCGGAGUGCGAAAGUCAGCCGAGGUCGCCCCGCCCAGGACAGAGAAGGGCUGUGGUCGGCUGAUCCGCGGCAUUCCCGGGAUGGCGGCGGCGUGGAUGGCUCCGGCGCAGGAGUCUGUGACCUUCGAGGAUGUGGCUGUGACAUUUACCCAGGAGGAGUGGGGGCAGUUGGACGUGACCCAGAGGGCCUUGUACGUGGAGGUGAUGCUGGAGACCUGUGGGCUUCUGGUCGCACUGGGUGACAGCACAAAACCUGAGACCGUAGAGCCUAUCCCUUCUCAUCUGGCCUUGCCUGAGGAAGUCUCACUCCAGGAACAGCUGGCACAGGGAGUCCCAAGAUACUCCUAUUUGGGGCAGGCCAUGGAUCAAGAUGGGCCAUCUGAAAUGCAGGAAUACUUUUUGAGACCAGGGACAGACCCACAGAGUGAGAAACUCCAUGGGAAAAUGAGCCUUGAACACGAAGGUUUGGCGACAGCUGAUGGUAUUUGUUCAAUGAUGAUACAGAACCAAGUCUCACCAGAAGAUGCUCUCUAUGGAUUUGACUCAUAUGGACCAGUUACAGAUUCCUUGAUUCAUGAAGGGGAAAAUUCCUAUAAAUUCGAGGAAAUGUUUAAUGAGAAUUGCUUCCUUGUUCAGCAUGAGCAGAUUCUCCCUCGUGUGAAGCCCUAUGAUUGCCCAGAAUGUGGGAAAGCCUUCGGCAAGAGCAAACACCUCCUUCAGCAUCACAUCAUCCAUACUGGGGAGAAGCCCUAUAAAUGCCUGGAGUGUGGGAAAGACUUCAACCGCAGGUCACACCUCACACGGCACCAGCGGACUCACAAUGGAGAUAAGCCCUUUGUGUGCAGUGAAUGUGGAAGGACCUUCAAUCGCGGGUCGCACCUUACACGGCACCAGCGGGUUCACAGUGGAGAGAAGCCUUUUGUGUGCAAUGAAUGUGGAAAGGCCUUUACCUACCGCUCCAAUUUUGUCUUGCAUAACAAGAGCCACAAUGAGAAGAAACCCUUCGCAUGCAGCGAAUGUGGAAAAGGCUUUUAUGAGAGUACAGCCCUCAUUCAACACUUCAUUAUCCAUACUGGGGAGAGGCCCUUUAAGUGCCUUGAGUGUGGGAAGGCCUUCAACUGCAGGUCACACCUCAAGCAGCAUGAGCGGAUUCACACUGGUGAGAAGCCCUUUGUGUGCAGUCAAUGUGGAAAGGCCUUCACUCACUAUUCCACCUAUGUCCUGCAUGAAAGAGCCCACACUGGAGAAAAGCCUUUUGAGUGCAAAGAAUGUGGGAAAGCCUUUAGCAUUCGAAAAGACCUCAUUCGACACUUCAACAUCCACACUGGAGAGAAGCCCUAUGAGUGUUUACAGUGUGGAAAGGCUUUUACCCGCAUGUCAGGGCUCACAAGGCACCAGUGGAUUCAUACUGGAGAGAAGCCGUAUGUAUGCAUCCAAUGUGGGAAAGCCUUUUGUCGGACCACAAACCUGAUUCGACACUUUAGCAUCCACACUGGAGAGAAGCCCUAUGAAUGCGUGGAGUGCGGGAAGGCCUUCAACCGCAGGUCACCCCUCACAAGGCACCAGCGGAUUCACACUGCAGAGAAGUCCCACGAACCCAUCCAGAGUGGGAACGUUUCUUGUGAGAGCACAGAUCUCAUUCAACACUCCAUCAUCCACACUGAGAGUAGCCCAGUGAGUGCAGUGAAUAUGGAAACGCCUUCAAUUGCCGCUCAUUCCUCCUCACUCGACAUCAACGGAUUCAUAGUGGAAGAAACCCUACCAUUGUAACAGAUGUGGAAAGACUUUUUACGUACACUUCAGUCAACAUCCAAGAAUUCCUAUUAGCGAAAUAGUUUUUUAAUAUAACCACUGAAGAAAAUCUGUGGUGAGAGGAAACAUCUUACCAUCUGGUCAUUCAUACUGAAGAGAAACUCCAUAAGUAUCAUCUCUGUGGGAAAACCUGUUUUAGAUCAUCAUUUGUCAUCUAAACAAUUAUGUUAGAAAUUGACACAGCCAAGAGUCUUAUUCUACAUCUGAUAAUUCACCCAUGAAAGAGACCCAGUGGUUACUGUGCACUUAGGAAAACCUUCAGCCACAUCUUUCUUAUUAGUUUACAGUGAAAUGUUAUCUCAGGGACAUUCAAACAAAGGAGGAGGAGUCAUAGGGAAGAGAAAGAAAUGGAAGCACAGCUUCUUUCAGACUUCCCUGACAAGCCCAUGGCAAUUUGUCAUCCCCUCCUUAUUUUAUUUGGGAGAGGGAAAUGUUUCAGAAACAAAAGGGCCUCAUCCCCUUUAUUUUCCCUGUGUAUACAUUCACUGCUGUCCAGUGCUGUAGACAAACGGUUUGUUUGAAAACAUUUUGUGAAAGCCUGCUUUGUUCCACAGCAUUGUCUCCACUCUUGAGGAGCAGAAGCAUAUAUCUUUAUGAGAAAGAUGGAGGCUUGAGUUAUGAAAUACUUUUACAUUUAAGGAGAUAAAGGAUGUACAUAUGAAUGGGCACAUUUUACUGCACACUUCAGACGCUUUGACUUUUUUAAAAAAAUUGUUUCUCCGUGUGUCUUUAACCACCCAGUACCAUACUUUUUUCUUGAUCUGGAUCUACUUGUCAAUUUCUUCUUUAUUUUUCUGUAGGAUGGAGAUGAUAUUGUAGCUGUUUGUACAUAAUGUAAUCCAGGGAGUCCUAAUUCUUCCCUCUGAUUGUGGUUUCUCAGCUUUUUUACUGCUCUUUAGAGAGAGUAAAUAGUUCAAAAUUCACCUCAACAAUUUUCUAGAGGUCAAUUUGGAACCAAAAAUGAAAUAAGACAUGUAGCUAAAGUAAGUUAAAAGAUUAUGAUAAACUCAGAAAAUAAACACAGAGAAGGAAUCUCAUUUUUCAGUCUUACAGAAGAUUGUGUGAAGGCUGACUAUACAUAAAGUGACUGGAAUUUUAACAGGUGAACCUGCAUAUGUAUAUGCAGGUAGUUGUCACCAUGGAUUGAGUCCAGUCGUAGUAAUUAAUAUGUUUAAUCAGAAUAUUUUGGAAUUUCUCUUUUGGUAUUCUUUUUGUUUCUUUUAUUGUUUUUAAUUGACAAUGUUUAUGGGGUUUGGUGUGAUAUUUCAAUACAUGUGUGCUAAGAGUAAUGAUCAAAUCAGGGUAAUUAGCAUAUCCAUCUCAAUCAUUUAUCAUUUCUUUGUGUUUAGAAACAUUCACAGUCUGCUUUUCUAGCUAUUUGAAAAUAUAAAAUGUAUUAUUGCCAAUUGUACUCAUUCUGCAGUGCCACAGAACACUACAACUUAUUCAAAUGGAAUCUUACUUGCUGUAAUUUUGUAUUUGUUAACCAAUCUCUAUCUGCCUCUCUGCUGUCCUUCCCAGCCUCUGGUUACCACCAUUCUCAACCUUUUAUGCUUGCAUAUGAGUAGAAACAUGGAGUAUUUCUCUUUCUGUGUCUAGCUUAUUUCACUUAAUGUCUUUCAAGCUCAUUCAUGUUGCUGUGAAUGACAGGUUUAUUUUUCAUGGCUGAGUAGUAUUCCAUUGUGUAUAUAUGCCAUGUUUUCUUUCUUCAUUCAUCUGAUAAUGGACACUUAGACUGAUUUCUUAGCUAUUAUGAAUAGUGCUUCAAUAAACAUAGGAGUGUAGAUCUCUCUUUGA